GACUCUGUCAUUACAUGGAGAGGCCCCUACAUGAGAAUAAAGUUAGUGUACAAAGGAGAGUAGAGUGGGAGAGAGUAAAAACAAGAGUCUAGUCAAGAAUUUGAUUUCUUUCUCCUGCUCUACCUCUUGGACUUCCAACUUCUGUGAGUCAACAUAGUGCCUCUUGCAUUUAAGAAACAUCUCAUCACACUCUUAUCAGCAUUGAGUUUAAAUUUCAAUUAGUGAGAACUGAGGAAAAACCAAGAAGCCUGCAUUCCACAGUGUCUGCAGGAAAAAUGAUGAGAACUCUCAUCACCACACACCCACUGCCCCUGCUUCUAUUGCCGCAGCAGCUGCUGCAGCUGGUGCAGUUUCAAGAGGUGGAUACAGAUUUUGAUUUCCCAGAAGAAGAUAAAAAAGAAGAAUUUGAAGAGUGUUUGGAAAAAUUUUUUAGUACAGGGCCCGCCAGACCACCUACCAAAGAAAAAGUCAAAAGACGUGUCCUUAUUGAACCUGGAAUGCCACUAAAUCAUAUAGAGUACUGUAACCAUGAAAUCAUGGGAAAAAAUGUUUACUACAAACACCGUUGGGUGGCAGAACAUUACUUCCUUCUUAUGCAAUAUGACGAGCUCCAAAAAAUCUGUUACAACAGAUUUGUGCCAUGUAAGAAUGGAAUUAGGAAAUGUAACAGGAGCAAAGGUCUUGUAGAAGGAGUGUAUUGUAAUUUAACAGAAGCAUUUGAAAUACCAGCGUGUAAAUACGAAUCACUUUAUAGGAAGGGCUACGUCCUUAUCACUUGUUCAUGGCAAAAUGAAAUGCAAAAACGUAUUCCUCAUACUAUAAAUGAUCUCGUGGAGCCACCUGAACACAGAAGUUUCCUCAGUGAGGAUGGUGUCUUUGUCAUAUCGCCCUAGCAGAGCGUUCUCUGAGAGCUUAGGGUGGGAGGAAUAUUUCUCUCCAUACUGAUCCUUAUAGAUCAAAGUUGAGAAUGGUAAUUUUGCUUCCAUUCACUUUAAUCACCCACCUUCCUUUCUUCCUUUCCCAACACCUCACAAAAGCACCUUAGGCUAGGUUCACAGACGGUGCUCUGAGAUGUGGUCUCAUGCAGGUCCCCUAAGUUAGCAUGCCUUGAAUGUGUUACGGAUACAGAUGCCUGCAGUGGAAGGAUGACCAGCACCAAGAGGAAAAGGAAAUGGUUGCCUGAAGUGUGCUCCAAAGACACAUCCAUGUGAUUCUCUAGUUCAGCAGAAAGAAUAAAAAUUGCUUCAAUCUA